GCUCACAACUGUCUGCUGCGCCCGAAAAACAAGUCGGUGCGCUGGGGACCCGGGGCCGGGGCCGCCUUACUCCGGCCUAGCCCCGCGGCCCUCGGUGCGGGCUCCAGGGCAUGCUCGGGACCCCCCGCGGCUCCAGCCCAGACGCCCCGGCCUCAGGUCUCGGCCCCCGCUUGGGGCCCCGGCCGUGCGGCCGGAGGGAGCGGCCGGAUGGAGCGGAGGAUGAAAGCCGGAUACUUGGACCAGCAAGUGCCCUACACCUUCAGCAGCAAAUCGCCCGGAAAUGGGAGCUUGCGCGAAGCGCUGAUCGGCCCGCUGGGGAAGCUCAUGGACCCGGGCUCCCUGCCGCCCCUCGACUCUGAAGAUCUCUUCCAGGAUCUAAGUCACUUCCAGGAGACGUGGCUCGCUGAAGCUCAGGUACCAGACAGUGAUGAGCAGUUUGUUCCUGAUUUCCAUUCAGAAAACCUAGCUUUCCACAGCCCCACCACCAGGAUCAAGAAGGAGCCCCAGAGUCCCCGCACAGACCCGGCCCUGUCCUGCAGCAGGAAGCCGCCACUCCCCUACCACCAUGGCGAGCAGUGCCUUUACUCCAGUGCCUAUGACCCCCCCAGACAAAUCGCCAUCAAGUCCCCUGCCCCUGGUGCCCUUGGACAGUCGCCCCUACAGCCCUUUCCCCGGGCAGAGCAACGGAAUUUCCUGAGAUCCUCUGGCACCUCCCAGCCCCACCCUGGCCAUGGGUACCUCGGGGAACAUAGCUCCGUCUUCCAGCAGCCCCUGGACAUUUGCCACUCCUUCACAUCUCAGGGAGGGGGCCGGGAACCCCUCCCAGCCCCCUACCAACACCAGCUGUCGGAGCCCUGCCCACCCUAUCCCCAGCAGAGCUUUAAGCAAGAAUACCAUGAUCCCCUGUAUGAACAGGCGGGCCAGCCAGCCGUGGACCAGGGUGGGGUCAAUGGGCACAGGUACCCAGGGGCGGGGGUGGUGAUCAAACAGGAACAGACGGACUUCGCCUACGACUCAGAUGUCACCGGGUGCGCAUCAAUGUACCUCCACACAGAGGGCUUCUCUGGGCCCUCUCCAGGUGACGGGGCCAUGGGCUAUGGCUAUGAGAAACCUCUGCGACCAUUCCCAGAUGAUGUCUGCGUUGUCCCUGAGAAAUUUGAAGGAGACAUCAAGCAGGAAGGGGUCGGUGCAUUUCGAGAGGGGCCGCCCUACCAGCGCCGGGGUGCCCUGCAGCUGUGGCAAUUUCUGGUGGCCUUGCUGGAUGACCCAACAAAUGCCCAUUUCAUUGCCUGGACGGGCCGGGGAAUGGAGUUCAAGCUCAUUGAGCCUGAGGAGGUCGCCAGGCUCUGGGGCAUCCAGAAGAACCGGCCAGCCAUGAAUUACGACAAGCUGAGCCGCUCGCUCCGAUACUAUUAUGAGAAAGGCAUCAUGCAGAAGGUGGCUGGUGAGCGUUACGUGUACAAGUUUGUGUGUGAGCCCGAGGCCCUCUUCUCUUUGGCCUUCCCGGACAAUCAGCGUCCAGCUCUCAAGGCUGAGUUUGACCGGCCUGUCAGUGAGGAGGACACAGUCCCUUUGUCCCACUUGGAUGAGAGCCCCGCCUACCUCCCAGAGCUGGCUGGCCCCGCCCAGCCAUUUGGCCCCAAGGGUGGCUACUCUUACUAGCCCCCAGCGGCUGUUCCCCCUGCCGCAGGUGGGUGCUGCCCUGUGUACAUAUAAAUGAAUCUGGUGUUGGGGAAACCUUCAUCUGAAACCCACAGAUGUCUCUGGGGCAGAUCCCCACUGUCCUACCAGUUGCCCUAGCCCAGACUCUGAGCUGCUCACCGGAGUCAUUGGGAAGGAAAAGUGGAGAAAUGGCAAGUCUAGAGUCUCAGAAACUCCCCUGGGGGUUUCACCUGGGCCCUGGAGGAAUUCAGCUCAGCUUCUUCCUAGGUCCAAGCCCCCCACACCUUUUCCCCAACCACAGAGAACAAGAGUUUGUUCUGUUCUGGGGGACAGAGAAGGCGCUUCCCAACUUCAUACUGGCAGGAGGGUGAGGAGGUUCACUGAGCUCCCCAGAUCUCCCACUGCGGGGAGACAGAAGCCUGGACUCUGCCCCACGCUGUGGCCCUGGAGGGUCCCGGUUUGUCAGUUCUUGGUGCUCUGUGUUCCCAGAGGCAGGCGGAGGUUGAAGAAAGGAACCUGGGAUGAGGGGUGCUGGGUAUAAGCAGAGAGGGAUGGGUUCCUGCUCCAAGGGACCCUUUGCCUUUCUUCUGCCCUUUCCUAGGCCCAGGCCUGGGUUUGUACUUCCACCUCCACCACAUCUGCCAGACCUUAAUAAAGGCCCCCACUUCUCCCA